AAACUUUUUGUUGUUUCUGUUUAUAUUUUUUUGUACUAUGUCCUGAAGAGUUGUUACAGUUAUUAUUUUUGAUUGGUUCAUCAUUAAGUCUCUCUACUUAGGAUAAGAGUAGUUUACCCAUCCCACUUAUAGUGUUAUAAUAUUCUGUAUUUUUCUGUGUCCUUACUAUUACUAGUGAGUUUUGCACCUUCAGGUGAUUACUUAUUGCUCAUUAAUGUCCUUUUCUUUCUGAUUGAAAUACUCCCUUUAGCAUUUCUUACAGGACAGGCCUGAUGAUGAAAUCCCUCAGCUUUUGCUUGUCUGGGAAAGUCUUUAUUUUUCCUUUAUGUUUGAAGGAUAUUUUGGCCAAGAUGUACUAUUCUAGUGUCAAAGUUUUUUUUUCCUCCUUCAGCACUUUAAAUAUGUCAUGCCACUCUCUUCUGGCCUUUAAGGUUUUUACUGAAAAUUCUGUUGCUAGAUGUAUUGAGGCUCCAUUGUAUGUUAUUUGUUUCUUUUCUCUUGCUAUUUUUAGGAUCUAUUCUUUAUCUUUGAUAUUGGAGAGUUUAUUAAAUGCCUUGUGGUAAUCUUCUUUGGGUUAAAUCUUCUUGGUGUUUUAUAACCUUCUUGUACUUGGAUAGUGACUUUUUUUUGUAGGUUUGAGAAGUUCUCUGUUAUUAUCCCUCUAAAUAAAGUUUCUACCUGUCUCUUACUCUACCUCCUCUUCGAAGCCAAUAACUCUCAGAUUUGUCCUUUUGAGGCUAUUUUCUUGUAGGUGUGCUACAAGAAAAUAGAUUUUGUAGGUGUGCUUGCUUGAUUUUUAUUCUUUUUUUAAAUUUUGUCUCCUCUGGAGAUAUAUUUUCAAAUAACUUGUCUUCAAGCUCACUGAUUCUUUCUUGAAUCUCCUUGUUCAAUUCUGCUAGUAAGUGACUGGUGCGUUCUUCAGUAUGUCAAUUGCAUUUUUCAGCUCAAGAAUUUCUGCUUGUUUUUAAUUAUUUCAAUCUCUUUGUUAAAUUGAUCUGAUAGAAUUCUGAAUUCCUUCUCUGUGUUAUCUUGAAUUUCUUUGAGUUUCCUCAAGACAGCUAUUUUGAAUUCUGUGUCUGAAUGGUCACAUAUCUCUCUUUCUCCAGGAUUGGUCUCUUGUGCUUUAUUUAGUUUAUUUGGUGAGGACAUGUUUUCAUGGAUUGCCUUGAUACUUGUAGAUGUUUAAAUGUGUCUGGGCAUUGAAGAGUUAGGUAUUUAUUAUAGUCUUUACUGCCUGGGCAUGUUUGUACCUGUUCUUUUUGGGAAGGCUUUCCAGGUAUUCAAAAGGACUUAGGUGUUGUGAUCUAAGCUGUAUCUGCUUUAGGGGGCACCCCAAGCCCAGUAAUGCUGUGUUUCUUGCAGACGCAUAGUGGUACCCCCUUGAUGGUUUUAGUCAAGAUCUGGGAGAAUUCUCUGGUUUAUUAGACAGAGAUUCUUAUUCUCUUCCCUUACUUUCUUCCAAACAAAUGGAGUCUCUCUCUCUCUCUGUUCUGAGCCACCUGAAGCUGAGAGUGGAGUGACAUAAGCACCCCUGUGGCCACUCCCACUAUGACUGUGCUGGAUCAGACCUGAAGCCAGCACAGCACUGGGUCUCAUCCAAGGCUUGCUGUAACCAUUCCCUAGCUACCAGUUAUGUUUGCUCAAGGCCCUGGGGCUCUACAAUCAGCAGGUGGCAAAGUCAGCCAGGUUGGUGCCCUUCCCUUCAGGGUGGUGAGUUUCCUCAGGAUCUGGGUAGGUCCAGAGGUGCUGUCUGGGAGCCAGGGACUAGAUUCAAAAACCUUGGAAGUCUACCUGGUGUUCUAUUGCAUUGUAGCUAAGAUGGCACUCAAACCACUAGACGCAGUCCUUCCCCCUCUUCCUUCGCCUUUCCAAAUGCAGAGAAGCCUCACCCUGGGGCCACCACCACCACAGGCCUACAGAGUACUGCCAGACUACUGCCAAUGUUCCCUUAAGGUACAAGAUCUCUUCAGUCAGCUUGUAGUGAAGGCUACCCGGCCUGAGACUCACCCUGCAGGGCAGUGGGCUCCCCUCUGGCCCAAAGCAGGCCCAAAAAUGCCAUCCAAGAGCAAGUCUUCUAAUUGAGGGCCCCAAGAGCCCACUUGGUGCUCUAUCCAUGUGUGGUCAAGCUGGUACCUAAGGUGCAAGAGAAAUUCUUUACUUUUCCCUCUGCUUUUCUUAAGCAGGAAUCUUGUCCUGUAACCAUCACAGUUGGGAAUGUGCUGAGUUUCACCUGAAGCCAGCAAAUCUCAGAGGCUCAGCCAUGGCCCUUGAUGUAGUACCAGGAUAUUGCCGCUGGUUUUUCGGGACCCAAGGAUUCUUCAGCUAGUAGGUAAUAAAUGCUGCCAGGACUGGCUCCUUUCCUUCAAGGCAGUGUGUUCCCUUCUGGCCCAGGGUAUGUCUAGUAAUGUUAUCUGGGAGCUAGAGCAUGGAAAGGAGGCCUCAGGACUCUGAUCAGUGCCCUAUUCUGUUGUGUCUGAGUUGCUAUCCAAGAUGCAAGACAAAGUUCUCCCCAUUCUUCCUUCUCUCCUCAAGUGGAGGGAAGGGGUCUUUUGUGGUACUGUAAGCUGUACAGCCUGGGGUUGGGGAAGGGUGAUGCCAGCACUCCUUUAGCUGCCCCAGCUGGUAUCUCAGUAGGUCACGUGCCCCCAGGUCCACUGGCCCUGGGCCCAGUUCAGCACUAGGACUUGCCUAGGUGUUGUAAUCCUUGUGGACUAGACUGCCUUUCAAGUUUAUUUAGGAACACAGAGCACUUUAGCCCACAGUGGUAAGGAUUGCAGAAAUUCAAGUUUGGACUGCUGGGAUUGGAGAUUCCUCUCUGCCUAGGGCUGGAUUUAUUUAUUUAAUUUAUUUAUUUAUACUUUAAACUCUGGGGUACAUGUGCAGAAUGUGCAAGUUUGUUACAUAGGUAUACAUGUGCCAUGUUGGCUUGCUGCACACAUCAACCCGUCAUCUACAUGAGGUAUUUCUCCUAAUGCUAUCCCUCCCCUAGCCCCCACCCCCAACAGGCCCAGUGUGUGAUGUUCCCCUCCCUGUGUCCAUGUAUGCUCAUUGUUCAACUCCCACUUAUGAGUGAGAACAUGCAGUGUUUGGUUUUCUGUUCCUGUGUUAGUUUGCUGAGAAUGAUGGUUUCUAGCUUCAUCCAUAUCCCUUCAAUGGACACAAACUCAUCCUUUCUUAUGCCUUCAUAGUAUUCCAUGGUGUAUAUGUGCCACAUUUUCUUUAUCCAGUCUAUCAUUGAUGGGCAUUUGGGUUGGUUCCAAGUCUUUGCUAUUGUGAACAGUGCCACAGUAAACACAGGUGUGCAUGUGUCUUUAUAGCAGCAUGAUUUAUAAUCCUUUGGGUAUGUACCCAGUAAUGGGAUUGCUGGGUCAAAUGGCAUUUCUGGUUCUAGAUCCUUGAGAAAUCACCAUACUGUCUUCCACAAUGGUUGAACUAAUUUACACUCCCACCAACAGUGUAAAAGCAUUCCUAUUUCUCCACAUCCUCUCCAGCAUCUGUUGCUUCCUUAGAUACCAUCUCAUGCCAGUUAGAAUGGCGAUCGUUAAAAAGUUAGGGCUGCUUUAAAUGCUCCCUCUGUAGGUGGGUAUCAGCAAAUUUGGUAUGGUUUCUCUUUCUGCUAUAAUAGGGUGGCACUGAGUUCAAUGCCUCACAAUUGCGGUGCUCUCCCUCCCCCAGUGCACUGAAAUGCUCUCUGCAGCACACUGCCACUGCUGGGAGUGGGUGUGGGUGGUGGUGGUGAUUCGAGACUCCCUUUUCUACCUCUUCAGUGCCUCUUUCAGUGAUAUUAAGUUAAAGCCAGGUACUGUUAGUGCUCCCCUGAGUUUUGGUUCCCAUGAAGGUGCUUUUUUGGUGUGUAGAUAGUUGUUAAAUUGGUGUCCUUGUGGUGGGGACGGUCGAUGGAGCCUUCUAUUUUACCAUCUUGCUUUCCUCUUCCCCGGGUUUGAUUGCUAUAUGGUUACACUCAGUGCACCAUCGGCUUGAAAUUCCUUUAGUGAUUCCUUGCACUUAGAAUGUGAGCUAAUUUUCCAGAGUUAUUUUCUCAGUGUCCGCUUCCUUCUUGGCUUUGAAUAUUUCCAAUGUGCUCAAGAGAGAAUCUGUUUCUUGUAGCUCUCCUAAUUGUAUUCCCUAUUAUUUUCACUUGGUGCUUCUUAGCCUAGUGGAGGACCAGGGCCAAAUUCUCUGAUGUUCUGAUUAAGCAUUAGGCUUAGUAGACACUGUAUCACUUAGCCUCUAGUGUAUGGCUUUCAAAGGUGCUCCUACCCCUCUUCAAGCUGUAGUGUGUCUAGCAUGUAUUCUCAUCCCUCCCUCCGGGUAGAGCUUUCUGUUUCCUUCCCUUUAGAUGCAAUGAGUUUCCACAGUAUCCUGAUUGACAGUUUUUAUUAUACUUCUGUCUGAAGACUAAGACUUUUGUCCCAUACGGGAAAUAGAAGAGAUGAAACUGCGGAAAUUUAUCACUGACUGCCGUUUCUCUCUGCAGCCAGGAUCAUGAAGGAAGCUGUCUUGAGAUUAUCUCACAUCUUCUCUCUAAGUGUCUGGUGAGAUUCUUAGAACCUGCAAGAGGGUGCAAACUCCCCUGUAUUUACAGUCCCCAGGGUCUUUACACUCUCACAAUAGUCCACAUUUGUUCUGUAGAAAUGUAUCUAAAAGUUUUGCUUGAAUCCUUCUUAUCAGCUUAUGUGGCUUUCAGCAAUGUCUACUCCAGGGAAGCAAAUGCUUAAUAUAUAUUUCUCCCUGAAGAAUCAUGUCUUUCUCUAGAUUGCAGGUUAGUUUGUUACCCUGCAGCCACAGUUCUCAGACAAACUUAAUAAAAAUUAUUAAUUUGUAGUUUGAUAAGGGUGGGAGAAAUGCUUUUCAGUGCUCUACAUUUCUGAGUUGAAACUGGGGAUCUGGCUGUCUUGAUUUUGUCUCCGAUUUUUAUCAGAGAAUAAUCCAGGCUGCUUUAAAUACACAAAAACUAAGAAUGAACUCAACAUACAGCGGGGAUCAGAGGAUACUCAACAUAGAGAGCGGAUCGGAGAUCUGAACUUAUUUCUUUAGCUUUGUGAACCCUGAAUAUCUGAGACAAAUCCCAGUCAACUUAGAAAGUUUAUUUUGCCAAGGUUAAGGACAUGCGCCCGUGUCACAGGCUCAGGAGGUCCUGAAGACAUGUGCCCAAGGUGGUAGGGCACAGCUUGGUUUUAUACAUUUUAGGGAGGCAUGAGACAUCAAUCAAUAUAUGUAAGAUGAACAUUGGUUCCAUCCGGAAAGGUGGGACAACUGGAAGCAAAGUGGGGGGACAACUUGAAGCGGGUAGGGGACUUCCAGGUCAUAGGUAAAUAAGAGAAAAAAUGUUGCAUUUCCAUCAUUGUGGCUGAAAGCAACCAGGGAAAAGAGCCUGGGGUAACCACUGACACAAGUAACAAUAAGGAUGACUCUCAGAAUCAUCAUACUUGUGAAAAAAGCCAGACAUAAAGAGUGCAUGUUGUGAUUCCAUUUAUAUAAAAUUCUAGAAAAUGAAAACCAAUCUGUGGUGACGAAAAGCACAUCAGUGGUUGCCUGGGGCCAGGAGAAGAGGGAGCCAUGGACUGAAAAGACGCAUUAGGAUCUGUUUUUGGGGUGACAGAAUGUUCUGUCUGUGUAGUGUUUUCAUGGGUGGACACUGCCAAACUCAUUGAACUUUAUCCUUUAAAUGGAUACACUGUAUUCCACAUAAAUUAUAACUCAAUCUGGUUGAUAAAAAGUACUGAUGUGUGUAUUUAGGUCUUGCCUUUCCCAAUCGGCCUGUGGUCCUCUGGAGGAAGGGCCAUGUUGUCCUUGCCUGGGCUGCACUGAAGCAGUAACACAGUGCUGAGGAGGCCUCUGGCACAGAGAGACUGAGUGGGAAACAUGCUCUGCCUUUCACCAGCUGUGAUUCCUUAACUAGCAGCCUCUCCUUGGCCUCAGUCUACUCUCCAUAAUAUAGAGACAAAAAUGUAAUGUACAGAGUAUUUGGAGAGGUUAACGGGUAUAAUUCUACAUAAAAUUUUGAAAACAACGCAGGGUUCAUAGUAAGAACUUAAUACAUGAUAUAUAUUAUUAUUCCUUUUGGCAUUUAUUAUUAGUUAAAAACUCAAGGUAAAAGGAAUAUUUUUGAGUACCUACUGCGCCUCAGACACAGUACACUUCACUAAACUCAGUAAUACAUACAAAGUGAUUCAGAUGAUAAGUGAAUAUCUAAGGUUUUUCUCUACAUAGUUUUGAUUCUUUUUGCCUCUUUUAAUGUAGAAUUUCAGCAUUGUUUGUACGUUUGUGAGAAACAUACUACCUGAUUCUGUAGCAUUUUUUUUUUCUUCUAACAUAGCAGCACAUGUCUCGGGUUGGCAGAGGGGUCGUGAGGGAAGCCCAACGUGCAGUCAGCCUCCCAUCAGGGCAGGCAGGUGGGUCAACAGUGUGGCAAACACAGAGGGUGGCUGAUGCACAGAUUAAAUUCUUGCUUCUUUUUAAAAUAGAACAUGAAGUAAAUGAUGUGUCUUACAAGAUACCCAAAGGAAACAUAUUCACAUCUGGAGAGCCCCUUUUAGCCUCUUUUAUUAUAAAGCAAUGUAGUUGCAAAAGUGUAAUUUGACAGUAAAAAUAUUAACCUCUAAAGGCAACUUUCCCAGGAUGACAUUUACAAGCCACCUCACACAUGCUCACAGAUUAACAUGACACAAAUCAUCUGUUUUCAAUCUCCAUGUUCCUGCCCUCAGCUCUUCUUAUAUUAGGAUUGACAGCAUUUGGUUUUCAAUGUUCCUCUUGAGGCUCAGAGAGCCCUGAAGGUAUCAGUUAGAUGAAUGAUGGGAAUCUGGCUCUGAUCUUUAUUUUGCUAUGUCAUCCUGUCAUCUCCCCACACCCCUCCUUCCCCUGCCAAUAAAACACACAUGUACCUCACACAUAGAGAUCUUAAUUCUGAGUUAAAAGGCCAAUUGACCACUGGGAAUCCAAGGCCUCACAUUUAUCAGCUUUGUUCCUUCUGGUCUGUCUUCUCUCAUAAUAUAUGAAAUCACUUUCACUUUUCUUAAUGUCAUUACCAUGAUAACCUUGUGUAAGUCACCUUCUUUGCCUUCUUACAGAUACACACACUACUGAUGGUGGUGUACAGAAAUGAAUGGGUCUCAGAGGAAACAGUUGUGACAUAUUCAUUCACACACUCAGCAUCUAUUUAUUGAAUAACUUCUAUGGCGCUGUGCUAUUAGCAGAGACAGCAGGGAAAAGGAGAAAGGUCCAUGUUCUGAAGCAGAUUACCAUCAGGUGGGGAAGAUAGAUAAGAAACAACCAGGAGCAUUAGGAGAGUGGUAAUUAUUGUGAAGAAGUACAUUAUAUAACAGAGCAAUCUGGUGCAAUUAAUACAGUUUAAGUGACAUGAUAUAAGCAAUAGGAAGAGUCUAAGUAAUGGAGCAAUGUUGUAAAUUCAGUGUACACAGUAGCACACACAGCAAAUUAGAUACAGGAAAAUAGUGACCAGAGGCGGGUGCCAAGUUUAAAUUAGGAGUGGCUCCGGGAAUGCAUUCUGAGGGGUGGCAUUUGAGAUGCAGUCCUAUGUCAUUUAUAAUCCUUUUGGUGGCAAGUAACAAAACCACAUAGACCAAGAUGGCUUUAGCCACAAGAACGACAAUCACCUGAUAAAACGCCUCAAAGUCGGGGGGUCCAGGUGGGCUGGUCCAGCGGCUCCUCUAGGCCAUCGAGGGCCCGGGUUCCUUAGCUUCCGGGGUCAGUCUGGGCCACGGCUGGCUCCCUCAGGGCUCCGAGAUCCCUGCAGCAGUUCCUGUCGUCAGUUCCCACAGGACAACAUGCAGUGCGAGGAGGAGGCGCCACUUUCGGUGAGUCUCUUUGAUCAAGGAGAUGUUUCCCAGAAGCCCCAGUAGCCUUCUCACAGCUCACUGGCCAGAGUAAUAGCACAUGCUUUCCCCUAAACCAAUCAUUGGCAAAGCAGAUGCGGGUUUAAUGAUGGAGGUAGGGAGGCCUGUGGUGAAUGGAGGGCAGUGGAUUUCCUGAAGAAAACCUUAUUAGUAUUAGAAAAGAGGAAAGUGUAUGUGUGUCGGGCAGAGGUGCUGGUGCAUAGUUGACUGGCCAGUAGAAAACCACUUAUGAAGGACAUCAGAUCAUAUCCUCAGAAGACCAUGGCAUGGCCUUGGGAUGGGGCUAAGCCUAGGAGAGCUCAGGGGAGCAGUGAAGACACAUGAAGAGGGGCCUGUGCCGGGUAGGGAGGGCGUGCAAGGUGAGGCCAGAGAAGGAGGCAGGUCCAGGGCAUUAGGGCCUGGUAGGCCCCUGUAAGGUGUUUGGAUUGUAUCUGGUAUAGCAGAAGUUCCUGGAGAGGACAGAGGUGAUCCAAGCAGAGGAGACAGCCCUGGGCCAGCAGUCAGCAGUCAGGUGCCGGCUCACACACGCAAAAUGCUGUGCAAGAGGCGGUCCCUUUCUCUAUGCUGGAUUCAGUACAGGUAAAAUGAGGCUCAUGGCACCCACCUCGUGGCAUUACCGUGGGACUUACUGCAUUGAAAGGAGAGUGUUGCGGCAAUGAGGUCCUGUACAAGUAUGAGCUGUCUUGUUCUCAUUAUUUGAGAUAGUUAUAAAAUGCCUAUGAACACUGAAUUAGCGAGUACUGAACCUUUGCUUGUAGGAGAAAUAGACACACACACACACACACACACACACAUUUCUAAUAGUCUGUAAUCUUCUAUUACAAAAGAAAUAUUGAAGUUUGGAAGUGUUAGGUGACUUGUCUGAGGCUGCCUCACUAACAGGUGCCAGAGUAGGGAUUCAGAUUCUGUCCUACUGGAUCCAGCGCCCAAGCUGAAGCUUCCCACACAGUGCUCCACUGCCCCCUAUAUUGUCCAUGCUCUGGUCUUUGUAUGAGAGCUGAGACAAGAAGGCAGAGCGAGUACUUGCUUGACCUCAACUGGGGAUGCGUGCAUGGCAGGUGGUUCAAAAUUUUCCCCUCUCUGUGCAAUUCCACAAAUGACCAAAAAAGGAAGGUACUGCAAGUACUGACUUUGGGGUUACAAAUAACUUUUAGGGAGUAGAUGAGUUUGCAAAUAUGGAAUCCACAAAUAAUGAGGGUCAUCUGUAAUUGGUGAGACCAUGAAGUGAGAAACUCUGGUUUCUGUAUAUCUAAUAUAUCCUUUGUACGUUGUUAGAUACCUCAAGUCUUAGUACUCAGUAUGAUUAGCCUUAUUUGUGCUGUUUUAAUUGAAUUACUUAAAAUGGAGGCAUACACUUUUUUAAGGGUAUGCAUGUCCCAGGAGAAAAAACUCAAAAGAUAGUCAACAUAAAGAAUUGCUAAGCCCUCUUACUUUGUUAUGUUUUUAAUUAAUUUAUUUUUCCCAUAUGAGCUAUACAUCACUUCCUAAAAGAUGGGGCAGGUUUAAGACUGUAGUGCUCCGAAAGGAUGCAGACAGUUACAUUAUUUCAUUCCUUAUGAACAUAGAAAGGGCCUCACAGUUUCCAAAACUGGUGUGUUCUCUCCAGUGGGAUGUGAUUCAGAGUGAUUUGAUGUGUGAUUGGGGGUGGUUGGGUAGCAGUAAACAAGGGAGAACCGUAAUUUUCCACAAAUGCAAGAGGUUUGAGGUCUGCACUACAGAACAUUGGACUGAGAAAGUUCUGGCAAUAGGUGAUAACCACCUGAGCUAGGGAGAAGUGAGAGCAGAACUCCCCAAUGUAUCCACUGCAGGUUUCUAAAUCACAGGGGGCCUCAAUCUCUUUUUUUCUGAGCAGGGUUGGGGGGACUUCCUUCUCUCGAGGUAGUCUGCAUGCCACAGGCAGAACAAGCAGUGAGUUCAGGGGAAAUCAGAGGUCUUACUGAGCCUUCACCUUCUCCUAGUGCAAUGCUUCCUUGGGAAGGCAGAUAUUUCUCUAUAAUGGGGCUUCCACACCUUGAGUACCUAAAUGGAUGGCAGUCAGGCUCAGCAUUGUGUCAGCAUCUAUUAAAAAUAAGAACAUGACCCUCCACUCCAUUUUCUUCUCUGAAUGGAGAUCUUGUUCUGAUUAUUCUCUUUACAGUCCUGGGCACAAUGAAGCAGAUUUAACUGCCUCAAACAUGCUCUAAAAUACAGCUAAUUUGCUUGCUUCAUUGUUGUUCUUCUCUCUCUUUUUAUAAAAUAAAGCAAAGAGAGGGAUAGAAGUAGAUUCUUUUCUUUUUUUAAUUUGAAAAGUUAAAGAAAUGCCAUAUUCAGCUCCCUGUGGAAUUUUGGGGAUGAGAGACACAUUAGCUAUCAGGCCUAAUGGUAGCUCUAUCUACUACCAUCUUAGGCCUGGAAGGAAAAAGACUUUAGACUGCUAAGUUCUGACAGGAUAGGAAAGGGGCUCCAAAAAUGAACUUAGCCAGACUCCAGUAACUCUUCAGCAAUCCUUGUUCAUUGCUUUGUGGACUGGGAUUAUCAAGUCAAAGUCUCAAUGAUUUCAGCAGAUCUCCCAAUGAGCAGCCUAUGUUAAUUAUACUUAAGGAUUCCUAAAGACGUCAUUGGUGUUGAGAAGUGGAAGUGACAAGGAUCCAUCCCUGUGACUGGGGAUGCAGGGUGAGUCUUAAGUGUCCCAUUAGCUAUUUUCUCCUUGGUUUCCAUGUCAAGCUACAGUGUAGAGCUGUUGGGUGGCAAAAGGCCGGUUUCAUUUCCAAGGAAGCACAUUCGUAUUAGUGCCAUUUUUUUUUGGCGGGGUGGGUGGCGAGGUGGUAAUUUAUCUCAAACCACUUGGAAGUUUACUCUUUAAGUUUGGAAGUGGGCACUUCUGACAUUGUUCUUGAGCCAUUCACUUGACCAUGUCAAAUAGGCAGUUGGGCACGUGUGUCUGGGGCUCAGAAGGGAGGCCUGAGUUGUAGUUACAGAUUCAAGUGAGGAAGAGAAGCAACAAGAAUAAGUCCCAGUUUCUGGCUUGCAAAAGUGGGGCUGUGGUGGCCCCACUGGUUGAGGUGGGGGCCCUGCCAGCAGCACAGGCUUGACACUGCCCCUCAGCAGUAUGAAUGCAAAGGUUGCACAAUACUUUUUAUUUUCUGUCCUCUGCUCAUGAAACGAUUUGUGAUCCCUCUUUCUUCUCUCUACCUAGUUACAUAAAUACAUUUUCCUGAUUGUCCAGGAGAGAAAGUCAGCCACAAUUUAUUUGCUUAUCCUGAAAAUGUGAAGUAAAAUGGGGACUUAAAUGGUCUAAUGCUCAACCUACUGAAGCAUGCACAUUAGAGAGGCCACCCCCAAGUGCUGAGUCAAAAGACCACGGUGAAAUGCCACAUUCGUUCUGCAAAAUUAUAGCUGAAUGGGGCAAAAAUAAUUAUAUCCAUGUUUCUAAUGCAUUUCACAACUAUUUUGCCUACCAGGAUUUUAAUCUAGUGCAAAGCUCUCCUGAUUUUUCAGAGAACCUCAGUAUGACUUGAAUAAUGUGCUUUUUCAGUAACAUAAAAACCUUUUAUGCAUCUUCAGAUAUGGUGCAAGAGUGAACUAUGAGGCACCUGGGGUUUGAUUAGUGAUCGUUUGAGUACCUAAAAAAGGUUUCCAACAACUGUGAUUCCAUUUUUGUGAAUGGGAAGGAAAUGAAGAGCAAAGUGGACACGAUUGUGAACUUCACCCACCAGCACUUCACCUCCCAGUUCGAGGUCACUGUCUGGGCACCCAGGCUCCCCCUGCAGAUUGAGAUCUCAGACACCGAGCUGAGCCAGAUCAAGGGCUGGAGGAUCCCGGUUGCUGCCAACAGAAGGCCUACCCGGGAAAGCGAUGACGAGGACGAUGAGGAGAAGAAGGGACGAGGCUGCUCCCUGCAGUACCAGCACGCCACAGUGCGUGUCCUCACCCAGUUUGUGGCCGAGUCACCUGACUUAGGGCAGCUGACCUACAUGCUGGGCCCCGACUGGCAGUUUGACAUCACUGACCUUGUGACCGAGUUCAUGAAGGUGGAGGAGCCGAAAAUCGCUCAGUUACAGGACGGCAGGACCCUGGCUGGUCGGGAGCCGGGAAUAACCACGGUGCAGGUCCUCUCGCCGUUGUCUGACUCCAUCCUGGCUGAGAAGACGGUGAUUGUCCUGGAUGACCGAGUCACCAUCGCGGAGCUGGGAGUGCAGCUCGUAGCUGGCAUGUCUCUCUCCCUGCAGCCACACCGAGCAGACAAAAGGGCCAUCGUCUCCACAGCUGCUGCCCUGGAUGUUCUUCAGUCCCCACAGCAGGAAGCAAUAGUAAGUUCUUGGAUUUUGUUCAGUGAUGGUUCGGUGACACCUUUAGACAUUUACGAUCCUAAGGAUUAUUCUGUUACUGUCUCAUCAUUGGAUGAAAUGGUGGUGUCUGUCCAGGCAAACCUUGAGUCCAAAUGGCCAAUUGUGGUUGCAGAGGGUGAAGGACAAGGGCCUUUGAUUAAGUUAGAAAUGAUGAUAAGUGAACCUUGUCAGAAGACCAAGAGGAAGAGUGUUCUUGCCGUGGGUAAAGGAAAUGUCAAGGUCAAAUUCGAACCAAGUAGUGAUGAGCACCAAGGAGGCAGCAAUGAUAUUGAGGGCAUAAAUCGGGAAUAUAAAGACCACCUCAGUAAUUCCAUAGAGCGCGAAGGAAACCAGGAGAGAGCAGUCCAGGAAUGGUUCCACCGUGGCACACCUGUUGGCCAAGAGGAAAGUACCAACAAAAGCACAACCCCCCAGUCUCCCAUGGAAGGGAAGAAUAAGUUACUCAAAAGUGGUGGUCCAGAUGCCUUUACAAGCUUCCCCACUCAAGGGAAGUCACCGGACCCCAAUAAUCCUAGUGACCUCACAGUGACCUCAAGGGGGCUAACGGACUUGGAGAUUGGCAUGUAUGCCUUGCUCUGCGUCUUCUGUCUGGCCAUUCUGGUCUUCUUGAUCAACUGCGUGGCGUUUGCCUGGAAAUACAGACACAAAAGGUUUGCUGUGAGUGAGCAGGGCAACAUCCCCCAUUCCCACGACUGGGUCUGGCUUGGGAAUGAAGUGGAACUUUUGGAGAACCCUGUUGACAUUACACUCCCAUCAGAGGAGUGCACAACCAUGAUAGACAGGGGCCUGCAGUUCGAGGAGAGGAACUUCCUUCUGAAUGGCAGUUCCCAGAAGACUUUUCAUAGUCAACUACUCAGACCCUCUGACUAUGUCUAUGAGAAAGAAAUUAAAAAUGAACCUAUGAAUUCUUCGGGCCCAAAGAGGAAGAGAGUCAAGUUCACUUCCUACACCACCAUCCUCCCAGAGGACGGCGGCCCAUACACCAACUCCAUCCUGUUUGACAGCGAUGAUAACAUCAAGUGGGUCUGCCAAGAUAUGGGGCUGGGGGAUUCACAGGACUUUAGAGACUAUAUGGAAAGUCUGCAAGACCAGAUGUAAACUCCUUUCUUAUGUUUGUAUUCACCUUUAUGCCUUCUGUUUUUUGAAUGCUGGAGCAGUGAGUUUGAUCAGCAAUAGGGGAUGAUUUAACAAAGUUUGAUUUGUGGAGGUCUGGUGGGAUUCAUUUCUAAGCAGGUAAAAGAGGUUUGGAGAGCUAUAGAAGCUGGGUUUUAAGUUUGGAAAUGCCUCUAAAACAGCCACAUGUGGGGACUGGAGAAAUUCUAAGACAACAGUUUUAUGGACUGCCUGGUACGAGCUCAGUGCAAAUGUAUUAAACCUGACCCCACAGACAUUGUUAGUCAUCUCGUGACAAAUGGCCAUGUGGAAUUAGAAAAGAUUUGGGUGUUGAUUUUUCUAUUUCUAGACCUUUUAAAGCACAGUGGACACUUAUUGCCCCUUGGCCUGAGUUUAGACAUACAUGAAAGAUGACUGAAUGUAGCUAUCCUGAUUUGUCAUGAGCGCUGCUCAUUAUUUUUAUAUACAUUUGCACCUGCACCUGUUCCUUUGACCUCUGGAAUUCUUUUUGAAACAUGAAGAGAAGAAAUUUCAGUCUUUUCCUUGAGCUCUGUUUGAUUUACACAUGAGUUUUCUUCCCUGGGAUUUGCCAUGCCAUGUUAUUUCCUGGGUCUCCAUGCAGGAUGUCAGGUUUUUCCAGUUUUCUGCACUUCAUCAUCUAGGGAUGGUAUCCAAGAAGCUUAUUCUCACUUUGUUUUUUCCUUCCUUUUGUUGUUGAACUUUCUUGUAUAACACUGGGACAAAGGGUUUUACUUAAAAUGUUAAUAUACAGUGAGGGAGGGCCAUCUCUUUACUGUUUUCUAUGUGAAGUUUCAAACAUUUGGAAAAAAGUUGUCAAUCACAAACAUUUAUUUUUAUUCUCUGCUUGUUGAAAACUCAUGGGGAACUCCUGGAGUGCAUUUCUGAGGGUAAAAAGGCCCCAACAUAGCUGUAUUUAUACAAGUGCUUUGUGGCCAACACAAUUUACUAUCCAAACUGAAGUCUUAAAGUAGAAUUGACCUACACAGAAAGGAAAUUGCCUAGGCAAUAGAUGCAGAUUACACUUUCCAUUUUACCAGAACAAAAGUUUUUUUUUUUUUAAAUAAGUAGAAUGACAGUUCAAGUUAGCAAUAUAUAGAAAUCCAUCCAUACAAUGACCAAAAUAAAUAAAUAAAUAAAACUCAAUCAUGACUUUGGCAGAGAUAAAACAUUGACAAGGGUGUGCAUUUGUGGAGAGAAGCAGUGGGUUUCCCCCCAAAAUCCAUACAAAUAAAUGACUAUUCCAGAACUCAAGAAGCAGCUAUUAUAGAAAAAAAAAUUAAAAACCACAGCUAUUGAAAAAUUAAAACGGCAAGAGAAAAAAAGAAACAACUCCUGCAUAAUGUUUAAAUAAAAAUGUUAUUUUAAUAGCAUCAUGAAUGGUCUUAAGGCAAAAAUUUCAGAUUAGCAAAAUGUGAUGACAUAUUUAUUAAGAUUGUAUUAUUGGAAAUGUAGACACUGGACUAGUAUGCCUCAUUAUGAGCUUUACUGAGCCAUUUGCAUCUCUAAGAAAUAUGAUUUUAAAGGCCCAAAGUAGGAAGGAUCUGCAGGGGGUCACCUGAAGCAGUGCCCUGACUCCAAAUGGCUGAUAACUGAGCUAAUCCAAGGAGAGGCGUUCAGUUGUUCUCUUAUUAUAGAUUUCCUUGGGUGGGAACAUGACAACCCCGCCUCCUCUAGCCAUGACGUGGCAGCCAAAAAGUUCUUCCUGUAUCUCUGGCCCACAGGACUGUAGUGUGUUUGGGAACAGUGCUGAAAUUGCAAGUGAUGUAGGCCUGACCUCCAGAGCCCAGCGUUCAGUUAGUUGUAUAAAAUGGGGCUUAGGAACCGAAGCUGAUGAAGUUCCAAAAGUAGUUCAGUUUGAUGGGAUAAGGAAGCAAGGAGAGCCAGGCAUUAGCUGCAAAAGGAGCUUGCAGAGAGAUGGCUGACACUUUAUGGGAAGAUUCCUCAGUCAGCCAAAAGCUUUUCAAAGAGUUUGGUGCAGAGGUAGCUCAGAGCCAACCAUCCAGGACCGAAGAAAGCUCAUGUGCUGAUUGACACAUAGCUAUCCAGGUGAGUCGGCUCCUUCUAUGAGGCUUUUCAAUCGUCUCUCCCUUUGGAUCUCUGGCAUUCCAGAAAGACUGGGAAUUCAUUUCUGAAAAUGAUGAACCUCCGCUGAAACGGGGAGGAAAUCUCUUACACACAUACAGCAGGGUCCUGCCCACUGGUAAAGUGAGACGUUGGGUAGGGGGUGUAACUGGGGAGGAGGUGAAGGAAAUUAUCCCUGCCAUGGGGAGUGUUAUUCAGGAACAUAAAAAUUAGAGCAUUCCCUCUGAUGGCAGUGCUUGACGGGGUGCAGGGAACAAACUGGGGAGCGUUCAAACAUGCCAGUGGUUUCUCAGCAGGGCUGGAAACUGGCCACAGUCCUGAAGAUGCUUCUUGUGACAACUUAGAGUCACUGGGAGUCACACAGCUCCUGUGUAGCCGCCUUUGCUCCUCUGUGUUAAAACCCAGUCAGUUCAAAAUAACAAUCAAAUGGAAGGCCAUGGGGGAAGGGUUCCUUCCACCAUAUAACCCACACCCAGAUGUAUAUAAACGCAUAUACAUACAUAUACCCGUGUGUGUGUGUGUGUGUGUGUGUGUGUGUGUGAAUACUGAAGAGCCAGACAACAAACUAUUUAGUAAGAAUCAACAGUGACUGUCAAUUGUUCUCAGAUUUGGCAUGGAUACUAUUUCUCAUGAAAUAAUGUCAUUAAAGUAUUUCCUCCUCUAAAUAUUUCCUGAAGAUCAUAAACCAUGGGUUAUAGCACCUUGUUUUCCAGCUAGUCAAUAUACAACUAUUAGGUGCUGUGCCCCAAAAUAUCUAAAAUGGGGGUAAAGAUAUAAACUAUUAAGCCAUGAAAUCUAAUUUUCUGGGGACCAUGCAUUUGCCUGGAUUUUCCAGGAUUUUAUGGCUGAUAGACCCAAAUUAUUAGUCUUGAUAAACAACCUGAACCAAACAUUUAUAAAGUCCCUUCCUCUCCCAUGGGAAUGGAAUGCUCAGACUCCUGCUGAGGGAGACACCAGCAAGCCUCUUGAGAAGGCACCAGACAGUGAACUCUGUGGUCACAUGAAGGGAGGUUCAGAUGCUAGACGACCAGCGUAUGACCUGGAACCAUUGAGGAUUGCAACCGCUGCCUCCAGGGUCCAGAUGUGCUGCAGUAGAGGGCAGAGCACAGGAAUCAAGAAGCAGCUGCCACACCAAAGAACUGAUGCUUAAACACACAGGUGUGUUGCAUUUGAGAGAAGGCAAGAAGAAAAGACAAUAGAAGGUUACCCUGGAAAAACAACACCUAGCAAACCUCAGAAUACUCCAUGUGUCCCAAGAGAAGGAAUAAUUGUCUUUCUAGCUGUUAUAUAUUGCACACUGGCCAGGAUAAAUUCCCAGACUAUAAUAAUCCUGACUAUGUAGACGGAAGUUUCUAUUUAUAAAGUCAUGCAGGGGGAAAGUUGAUUAAUUUUUGUCCCAUUGCCACAUCUGUAGACUAAGUAAUUUUUAACUUGCUAACUUUUAGAAUGUCCACCUUUGUGCAUUUUGGUAGCAUUCUUGUUUCAUUAUUUUAGAAAGGGGUCUUCCCAUUACUGGGAUGUCGGGGCCCUGUCAGAGAACUAUUAUUAAGGCUCUGUGAGGGAACUGUUCAGUCUCACAGCAAGGACCACAGAGCGUGGUUUCAUCUGAACCCUACAAGUCAGGGACACCAGUGUGUUUUCUACUCGAGUUACCUAAAAAUGGUCUCAAUUUUCCAUUUCAUUCUCUGUAAAUGACACAAUAGAUGGUUUAUAGACUCAGCAGCCCUCACCUUUUAUUAAAAUUAUAUAUGUGUGAUGUAAUGCAUAUCACCUGUCAUGUAAAGGGACGGUAUGGAUGGUGGAAAAGUUAUGCUAAAAUAUGGAUUGCAGAUAUUUUUGUAUGUAAUAUAGGCAAUAUAAUGAAACACCGAGUUUUUUAAAGUGAAAGCAUGCAAAAUCGUAGCUUUUAAAUGUACAGACAUCCCACUCAAAAAUAUCUAAACUGAUAGUGGGAAAAACAUUUGAGACCUAGUAACAUCAUGAAAUGCACUGAAUUUGGAAUUCUGGCCUAGAAAGGCUGUGGCUUAUGUUGGGAUUGAUGAUGGAAUCUGCCAGAACAUUUUCAUCUUAUUCUUCUUGACUUUUGGAUUUUUUUCUUUUCUUUUUUUCUGGAAAUAUUUCGGAAAUAAAGUGACUUCAUUUUUCAGCAUAAAAGUAUAUUCUAACCACAGGGUAACACAUCGUUUUUAACAUGAAAAUAAACAUUUAAACAUUCUUCAGUUGUUUCAUUAUUUUAUCUGCAUGUUCCAUAAAGCAGCUGUAUGGUUGGCUAUAAUAUAGAUUUAUUUUUUCUUUUCAGCCAGAGAUUUUAAUACCCUUGAUGCAGUAAUAAAUGGACAUCAAAAGAAAACAUUUCUUAAAAGUUGCCAACGUAUUUUACCUUGAAAACAUUUCUUAUUUGUUAUCCUAGUAGGCUGGGGAAAGCUUCUCUCCAGAUGUCUCAGAAAAAGAUCUCCUGUUUCUCAUGGCCCCGUCCAGGGUCAAACCAUGUUGAAAGUCAGUGCUGAAAUGCAUGAUGCUGCGGGUGUUUGAGAGCCUUUGACCUCUGUCCACCCUUUGGUCUUUGCUCGUCAAUGGCUUGGUCUUGUAUAUGUAUCUGGGGCAGGGGCUUUGUACUGGGCCCAGGGUGCUGAGCUUUCCAGAACAGGCAGAGCUCUAGAGACCUAAGAAAACCACAGGACAGGCGGGGAUUCUUUUUGAGAGGCUGAAGUAGAUGUUUCAGCUGAAAGAUGGGUGGUACACUUGCCAAGUGCCUAGAGGGGCUAGAGGCUCUCUGUUGGUGUGUGUGUAUUUCUUGAAACUGCAGAGUCAUUUUUGGCAUGCUGGCAAAUGCUACUCCUUGCUUUUAGGAUGAAUAGGGAUGCCUCUUUGGCGAUAAUUUGACGUGUCAUAAUAAAUGCCCAAUACCAAACCUAGUCUUUCUCCAGGCCCUUCAGACAUCAUUCAGGUAACUGGGUGUAAACACAGGAGUUGGCUUUGUGAAACUGAGGCAGGAUUUCCUGCCUCUAAACUAUUGGCAGCAAAAGAGCCAAAAAUGUGCUCCCAGGUGCAAAACCCCAGCCCCAUCAGAAUUGCUUCUCAGCACUUUGGGUAACUGUUUUGCACUAACAGCUUCCUCCUUGUCUUUUCCCUGGGAACAUGGGAGCACUGACACAGAACUCAACUGGUCCAGCCCUUUGGGAGGCCCAGGUGGGCAGAUCACCUGAAGUCAGGAGUUUGAGACCAGCCUGGGCAACAUGGUGAAACCCUGUCUCUACUAAAAAUACAAAAAUUAUCCAGUCGUGGUGGUGCAUGCCUGUAGUCCCAGCUACUCUGGAGGCUGAGGCAGGAGAAUCACUUGAACCUGAGAGGUGAAGGUUGUAGUGAGCCAAGAUCGUACCACUGCACUCUGGCCUGGGCAACAAGAGCGAGACUUUGUCUCAAACAGAAACAAAACAAGAAAAACAAAAAGAACUUAACCAGUUCUCCCCAGAUCUCAGCGUGCAUGCAUAUAUAGAGUUUAGUAAAAUGUGUUUCAAAAAAAGAAGGAUAAAAGAAAGUUUGAAGUAAGAUUUGUAAAAGAAUGAACACUUUAGGUUUUGUGUGUGAGUGCAAAAUGUAAACACGGCAUUUGAAAUUUUUUGGUAUUGAAAUCCUUAAUGCCUGUUAGUUUCUUUAUGGUUUUAUACAAUUGAGAUAGGUUCUGAAGUUUUUUUGUUGUUUGCUUUUAGAAAUUUUUAAAAAUACAAAAAAAAAGCGCAGAAACAUUUUCAUCUGGGUUACUGUGUUUAUAGACUAUUCUAUGACUCAAGACAACUAGGACACCAUCAUUUUCCAGAUAAGAAAUAACAGUUCAAGUUCAUUAGGGAAAUUAUCUUCCCAGUCCAAGCAAGCAAUAAUGUUAUCAACUUACAAUAUUGGACAAUCUUCAUAUUCUAUGAGAUGCCUUUAAAAUUUCUUUGGAUUUAAUGCUGCUCUUGGUCAGUUGUUCAAAUGAAACAUUGUAAUUUCAUGUUAACGACAAGAGUCUCACGGGAGUCUCUUUAGAUGCUGCAGGAACUGAGAGGAUAGAAGACCUCUCUAUACAUCUACAUUGCCCAUUGGAGUAAAGCACUUUACAGAGAGAUGGAUGCCGCUUUGGGAUUUGGGGUCUAUGUAAUGCUGAUUUUUUUCAAACCUGUUUGGAAAUAUUACUUCUUUGGGAUGGCUGAAAUAACUUUUGACCUGACACAUCUUUCUGUACUUCCUGUGGCCAAAAAAGCAAGUGAGACUUUCUGUUUCCCAUUGUAAGGCUGGAGCUGAAAUAGUCUGCCACGUUAUUGUUAUCUCCUUUGUAAGAAUUUGACUUUCUGAAUGAAAUAACAGAAUGCCAGUGUCAACACUGACCAUAUGAUAUAGUUAUUUCACUUAGAGAUGCUUCCUCAAAGAGCGUGCCUUUUUCCUCCAUCAUAACCGCUUUAGGAUCUCUGUUUUAUCCAUGUAUUUCCCACAUAGUAGAAGCAUUUUCCAUUUCCAUGAAUAUUACAGGCUGAGAAGGAGCACACAUCUGGCACUGAUAAGCACACUGGCCCAGGCACUCAGCCUUCUCAUUUCAUUAAUCUGGUUGGUGACCGUUUCCAUCGGGCACACCUGGAAAUGUCCAUCGGACAUAUUGCCAUCUCAGUUGCUGCAGUGCAGUGAAUUACCCCAGAGCCACCAGUUCACAUGCCCAAAGAUGAACUGGCCCAUGGAGGGACUUGAUUGCCAAGUGACUUCCUUUCUGUAGUUAUCCUCUGCUGUGACCCUUAUUUUGGACUUCUAGCAAGGGCAUUCAGUGUGGAUUCCAAGAACAAAACCAAUUGUCCAACCUCCAUUACAGGGGUCUUCUAGGUAUUCCCCACACAUUAUUUGUGGGCAUAAGCAAACACCAUAACUAUGAAAGGCUGAGAGUGGAGAAUUAAGUCAUAAGGAAAUGAUCAAACCUAGGGAAAAAUAAGUGGCUAUAAAACACUGAAAGAUAGUCACAUCCACAUAGCGUGUAUCAUGCAACAGACCCGUGCUCUUAGAGGGAGGUAGUGUGUGUCUUCCCAUGGCAAAUAAUUUUUACAAUACUGCUCAUGUUUAAUGUGUGUCUACAGGGCAUGCUGUUGUCUCAAAAUUGAAAUGUGCAUCUUAGGUAUCAGUUCCCAGCCUCAGACUCUUCUCAGGCAGGUGGACCGGAUCUCAGCUGCAGAACAUAGUGAGUGGCCAAACCUACACAGCCCAGCCAGUAGUGUGCUUUGGGGUGAUUGCAAGGCAGCAAACAGUGGGGACAAGUUUUGUCUGGCAUUUGAAAAGGUGUUAUCCCUUACUUUCCACAUUUCUGAAUUGGAUUCUUGUUCCCUGGUAAACACCAGAUAUUAUAAACAGAGCAUGCUGUUAUGACAUUGUGCUUCUAUAUACCUUUUUGUAUAAUGUAUCUAUCUCAUUAUAUUACCUAUGGUUUCAGUAUGAUCUGUUGUGUAUGUUCCACCGUAUAUUUAAUGUCUCUGUAAAGGCACUUCCAAACAUUUUGAAAACGAAGAAAUAAAACAUGUUGGAUGAUUCCUUGU